GAGCCCUAUUCACACCUCGGCCAGGCUGCGGUGGCCAGGACUGGUUUGGGAAGGCAGGGCCCCGGUGUGCAGCCACAGCCAGCAGCCUCCUACCUACACAAGGGUGUUCGGGAGCAUCUCAGGGCCGAAGACUUUGCUGCCUGCCCUGCCAGGACUUUGUCCUCACCCCUGGCACCAUGCAGCUCCAGGUGUUCUGGACUGGGCUGGAAUACACCUGCCGGCUCCUGGGCAUCACCACUGCUGCAGUGUUGAUCGGCGUGGGCACUGAGACCUUCCUCCAGGGCCAGUUCAAAAGCCUGGCUUUCUAUCUGCUGUUUACAGGAGCCGCUGUCUCCAUAUGUGAAGGGGCCUACUUUGUGGCUCAGCUGCUGGCCAUCUGCUUCCAGUGUCAACCAGGGUCCCUGGCAGACAGAGUAAGGGAGAAAGCCCACUGGCUGGGCUGCUUCCAGAAGUUCCUGGCCUACCUGCUGCUGUCGGUGGCCUGCUUCCUCCACCCGGUCCUGGUCUGGCACGUGACCAUCCCAGGCUCCAUGCUCAUCAUCACCGGCCUGGCCUACUUCCUUCUGAGCAAGCGGAAGAAGAGGAAAGCUGCCCCCGAGGUGCUGGCCUCCCCAGAGCAGUACACAGACCCCUCUAGCAGCGCUGUGAGCACCACCGGCUCUGGGGACACAGAGCAAACCUACACUUUCCAUGGGGCCCUCAAGGAGGGGCCCAGCUCCCUUUUCAUCCACAUGAAGAGUAUCCUGAAGGGGACUAAGAAGCCCAGUGCCCUCCAGCCCCCCAACACCCUGAUGGAGCUGAGCCUGGAGCCAGCCGACUCCCUGGCCAAGAAGAAGCAGGUGCACUUUGAAGACAACUUGGUCCGCAUAGUCCCCUCCCUCGCCGAAGGUCUGGAUGAUGGGGACAGUGAGCCAGAGGAGACCACCUCUGACACGACACCCAUCAUUCCCCCUCCCCAGGCCCCACUCUUCCUGUCAUCUCUUACAGCCACCGGCCUGUUCUGAGCGCUUGCUCCAGCCUGGAGGACGCUCAGUGAGGGGUCUACCUAGCUCAAUGGCCCUCCCUGGAGUUUCAGGGUCUUCUCUGGUCAGCUUUUCAAGGGGUAACCAGACACCCCCACACUGGCUGGGCCCCUGAGGCCAUCAGGAGGUGUGACUGGCCAGCAUUUCUGGAGAGGCCUCGAGGGAGGCACAAACAAGGCUCACGCCACCUCAAGCCAGCACAAGCUCCUUCCUCCUGGCCACAGGUGGGGAAACCCUUAUGCUUCCCCAACAAGACCAUCACUGCCACUGCGCACGAGGCUGCAGGUGCCAUUGACUCAGCCCAGAAGGGACAGAGGAUGUCUGCCCAGCAAAAGCCUCUGGGCUUUUCUUACUCCCAACCCAGGGCACAACACUCAGUGAGGAACCUAUGGUCCACCCAUCUCUGCAGGCCCAGGGAAGUGUCAGUAACUUAAGCAUCUCUAAGGCAGAGAAGGUGGCUGUGGGUCUUGACCAACCAAGACUGCUCAGGGUCGGGAGGGGAGGCUGCAGGCCUCUGGUGGGAGCAGCCGGGCCGUGGGCCACAUUCUCUGCAUGCUCUAGGGCUGGGGCUGAGCUGCUCAGGAAAACAAUGCCGCUCUGUGCUCACUGUGGGAAAGCCAGGCCAGAUGAGCAAAGCUCAUUCCAGAAACAUGGCUGGGGACUUCCAGCCUCCUUACCACAUGGCCUUUCCAAGAUUCCAGGUUGAUGAUGCAAACUGAACGCAGUGAAUGCCAGGGCCCAGAAGGCAAUGUCUGCUGUGGGCAGGACCACAGAGGCUGCCCAGGGGUGGCACAGCACAGAGAAGUGUCAGUGCCGUGUUUAGGCACUUGGUAGCAGAAUAGGUGAUAAAUAUAAAUGUCUUCAAAAUGAAAGGAAGUGAGGGGGGAAGAAGAGGAGGGAAAAUGGGAGGAUAGGAGGAAGUGGGCAGGCAGGCAAGUUCUCUGCCAUGGGGCCACGGAAGUGACAGUUAACCCAGAAGGAACAAAGACAUCUGAAUCAGAUAUUCCUUUGUAAAUCUGUAAAGGAUUUGCAAUAUAGGCUUUACUUCUAAAAAUUGUUGUCGGGUCCAUGAGGCUGUUGCCAGGAAGAGCACACACACCAUUCUUCAUGGCAACUGCAGUGAGGGAGCAGUCAGGAGGAAGAGUCCUGUGGCUUCUCAGUCCCUGUGGAGGCUAACGCAAAGCUCUGUAGAACAAGCCUUAGAGUGCAUGCUCUAUGGUCUAAUGAGAAACUUGUGUUUGUGCUUGCACACGUUUCAAUGUUCCCUACAGGAUAUUUUACAAAGGUAUGAAAAUAAUGGCCAACCAGAAGCUAGUAUCAGUUUGGGGCCUAAAUGCAGCAGGUGUUCCUGAUAAGCAGAUAAGCAGAGCUCUUCCUGCAGUAGCCCAGGUCUCACCAAAUGACAAAUGGCUAAUCAAGACACUCCUGCAAGCCCUUGAUGGUGAGAGCUGCAGAGCUGUUUCUUCAGCUGCCAUCAAGGCAGGACCUCAGGACCUGACUGUCUACAGUCAGGGAAUAGUGAACAAUAUGGGAUAUGGGUAUAGGUAGGUGGUAGACAAGGAUCGUGCCCCAUGGCUGAUGGGCCGGGUGUCUCAGGCAGGCCCCCUGUGCACAGAAAGAGCCUAAGUGCAGAGAAGCCAGGCAUCUUUCCCCUGUCAACUGUGGAAGGGGAAUGUGAUGGCCACAGACACCCUCAUGGCACAGACAUGGCCAGCCUCUGACGUUCCUCUGCAUCAGAGUAGUUCUGUCCUCGAAGCCCCAGUCAGCAGAGCUGGAUGACCAGAUCGCAAGAAGCAAACCAGAAAGUGUGAUGGCAGAGAUGUCAGAUCCCGUUUAAUAAACACUUCAGUAAACCCAA